AGUCCUCCCUUGGUGGCCUCGCCGCGGCUCUGCUGGGAGACCCGGCGCUGGCGGCUGCUGAGGCCGGAGCGGAGGGCCCGGGAGCGUGGGAGCAGGAGGGUGGCGCGCAGCCGGUUUCGCGUUUGGUCGGCCAGGGAGCUGCCUUCCCACCAGCCGGUCGAGGAAACAACGGGUCGGGCUUCCGGGGAGAGGGCCCACACAGUCUCCUCGCCGGCACCGGCCUCCUCCAUUUUUCCGGGCCUUGCGUGGAGGGUUUUGGCGGAUGUUUUUGAACGAAGGAAUGUCAUCGGGGCUCUCUCGAGCCCCUCACCCCGCCAGCUACUCUGGGGGUGGCGUGGCAUAGUGAGAGGAGCGCUAAGUUGUUGGGAGGCCUGGGUCCUUUUCCCCACGACUCUGAAAGAGGACAGCGUUCCCAAUGUCCCAGUUUAAGCGCCAGCGGAUCAACCCGCUUCCAGGGGGACGCAACUUCUCAGGCACAGCUUCAACAUCUCUUCUGGGCCCUCCUCCUGGUUUGCUCACUCCUCCUGUGGCCACAGAACUGUCCCAGAAUGCCAGGCACCUUCAGGGUGGGGAGAAACAGCGGGUCUUCACUGGUAUUGUUACCAGCUUGCAUGACUACUUUGGGGUUGUGGAUGAAGAGGUCUUUUUUCAGCUAAGUGUGGUGAAGGGCCGUCUGCCCCAGCUGGGUGAGAAGGUGCUGGUGAAGGCUGCAUACAACCCAGGCCAGGCAGUGCCCUGGAAUGCUGUCAAGGUGCAAACGCUCUCCAACCAGCCCCUACUGAAGUCCCCAGCACCUCCUCUUCUGCAUGUAGCAGCCCUGGGCCAGAAGCAAGGGAUCCUGGGAGCUCAGCCUCAGUUGAUCUUCCAGCCUCACCGGAUUCCCCCACUCUUUCCUCAGAAGCCUCUGAGUCUCUUCCAAACAUCCCACACACUUCACCUGAGCCACCUGAACAGAUUUCCUGCCCGGGGCCCUCAUGGACGGUUGGAUCAGGGCCGAAGUGAUGACUAUGACUCCAAGAAACGCAAACAGCGGGCUGGUGGAGAGCCCUGGGGUGCUAAGAAGCCAAGGCAUGACCUGCCUCCUUACCGGGUCCACCUCACUCCUUACACUGUGGACAGCCCCAUCUGUGACUUCCUAGAACUCCAGCGCCGUUACCGCAGCCUCCUGGUCCCCUCAGAUUUUCUGUCCGUGCAUCUGAGUUGGCUAUCAGCCUUCCCCCUGAGCCAGCCCUUUUCCCUCCAUCAUCCAAGCCGGAUCCAGGUCUCUUCUGAAAAGGAGGCAGCUCCAGACGCUGGUGCUGAGCCCAUCACUGCAGACAGUGACCCCGCUUAUAGUUCGAAGGUACUGCUGCUCUCUUCCCCGGGGUUGGAGGAAUUGUAUCGUUGUUGCAUGCUCUUUGUGGAUGACAUGGCUGAGCCAAGGGAGACGCCAGAGCAUCCUCUGAAGCAGAUUAAGUUUUUGCUGGGCAGGAAAGAAGAGGAGGCAGUGCUGGUUGGGGGUGAAUGGUCUCCUUCCCUGGAUGGCCUCGACCCCCAGGCUGACCCGCAGGUGCUGGUGCGUACCGCCAUCCGCUGUGCGCAGGCCCAGACUGGCAUUGAUUUGAGCGGCUGUACCAAGUGGUGGCGCUUUGCCGAGUUUCAGUACCUGCAGCCGGGACCCCCCCGGCGGCUUCAGACAGUGGUGGUGUACCUGCCGGAUGUCUGGACCAUCAUGCCUACUUUGGAGGAGUGGGAGGCCCUGUGCCAGCAGAAAGCUGCAGAGGCAGCUCCCCCAACCCAGGAGGCACAAGGGGAAACGGAGCCUACUGAACAGGCACCUGAUGCCUUGGAGCAAGCAGCAGACACUUCUAGACGGAACGCAGAAACUCCAGAGGCCACCACACAGCAGGAAACGGACACUGAUCUCCCAGAGGCCCCUCCACCCCCCCUAGAACCUGCUGUCAUCGCACGCCCUGGCUGUGUAAACCUGUCCCUCCAUGGGAUUGUGGAGGAUCGGAGGCCAAAGGAAAGGAUCUCUUUUGAGGUGAUGGUGCUGGCCGAGCUGUUUCUGGAGAUGCUCCAGAGGGAUUUUGGCUAUAGAGUUUAUAAGAUGCUACUGAGCCUUCCUGAAAAGGUCGUGUCCCCACCUGAACCUGAGAAGGAGGAGGCGGCCAAGGAAGAAGCCACCAAGGAGGAAGAAGCCAUCAAAGAGGAGGUGGUCAAGGAGCCCAAGGAUGAGGCACAGAAUGAGGGCCCGGCUACAGAGUCAGAGGCCCCGCUGAAGGAGGAUGGGCUUUUGCCCAAACCACUCUCUUCUGGGGGAGAGGAAGAAGAAAAACCCCGGGGCGAGGCUUCUGAGGACCUGUGUGAGAUGGCCCUGGACCCAGAACUGUUGCUUCUGAGGGAUGAUGGAGAGGAGGAGUUUGCAGGAGCAAAGCUGGAGGAUUCGGAGGUCCGGUCCGUUGCCUCAAACCAGUCAGAGAUGGAGUUCUCUUCACUUCAGGACAUGCCCAAGGAGCUGGAUCCCUCUGCUGUGCUCCCCUUAGACUGUCUGCUUGCUUUUGUGUUCUUUGAUGCCAACUGGUGUGGCUACUUGCACCGGCGAGACUUAGAGAGGAUCCUCCUUACCCUUGGGAUCCGGCUCAGUGCAGAGCAGGCCAAGCAGCUGGUCAGCAGGGUGGUGACCCAGAACAUCUGCCAGUACCGGAGCCUUCAGUACAGCCGCCAGGAGGGCCUGGAUGGUGGCCUUCCCGAGGAGGUGCUCUUCGGAAACCUGGACCUGCUGCCCCCUCCUGGGAAAAGCACGAAGCCAGGUGCUGCCCCCACAGAACACAAAGCCUUGGUGUCCCACAAUGGCAGCCUGAUUAACGUGGGGAGCCUGCUGCAGCGCGCGGAGCAGCAGGACAGCGGCCGGCUCUACCUAGAGAACAAGAUCCACACACUGGAGCUGAAGCUGGAGGAGAGCCAUAACCGUUUCUCAGCCACUGAAGUAACCAAUAAGACGCUGGCGGCAGAGAUGCAGGAGCUGCGAGUCCGGCUGGCGGAGGCCGAGGAGACCGCCCGGACGGCGGAGCGACAGAAGAGCCAGCUCCAGCGGCUGCUGCAGGAGCUCCGCAGGCGUCUGACCCCCCUGCAGCUGGAGAUCCAGCGGGUGGUGGAAAAGGCUGACAGCUGGGUGGAGAAGGAGGAGCCGGCACCUAGCAACUGACGGCCUCGCACGGAACUGCCAUCCUGUGAGGGCAGCGGUGGCGCCCGGCAAAGUUGGAGCCCUUGCGGUACCAGAAAGCAGCGAGAGCGAGACCUGGGAGCCAGGGCAGGGGUGGCUGACCCCAUGCUCAGCCUCUAGGGGACGGCAGGCCAUCAGGCUGGGGGCUGUGCUAUGUGGGAUGGAUGUGUGAGGAACCCCGGUUCCACUUAACAACUAAAUACAACAUCUUUUGCACCCCUAGAAUGUCAUUUUGCCCUCAACCUUGGUAUUUCUCCUGGGGCCCUUUUAGUCUUGUGCUGACUUUCUCCUGUCCUCUUCCAGUUUAGAAUAAGACAGGGGAGAAAAAGGCUUUUCGAGUGUGGGACAAGGUCUGAUGUCAGUGAACGGAACUGAAGAGCAAGACAUGGAGCCUGGCUGGGGCUAAGCAGCCCCCUCCUCCGGAUGGCACAGGCUCUGCUAGGUUCCGGACACAGGCUUCUGGGGGAAGGGUCUCCCUUGGCCAUCACGGGAAUGGAGUCCAUGCUAGAAAGAGCUCAGUGUUGGGCUGGGUUUGCCAGUAGAACACUGCGUUCCAGUCACCCCGGUCUUGCCAGAAGAAACCAGCACCUCUUUCCCGUGGCUCCUGUGUUCAGAAUGUGGUAUUGGCUCUGGCCCAGCCUUCUCCCCUGUUACCCAUAAUUCUUGCCUCUUUCCAUAAUCCGUGGUUUCAGUUUGACUUUGUAUAUAAAGUUGGGGUUUUUUUUUUUUUUUUUUGGCUUGUUUUUUAAAUAAACCAAAGUCAAAAACAAACUGAGAGUGUGUCCUCCACAGCUCUUCCUACUCUCCUAGGCUUGCCCGCGUGCCCUCCCACCCAGCGCCUCUGCUGGACCACGGUGCAGUUCGCUCCAGAAGGUGGGCCAGGGCCGGGGAGGUGCGCACACACCCCUGGCAUGCUGGGCUGCCUGCUGGAGGGUGCUGCUGCUCCGUGGAGGGCAGCAGGCCCAGGAAGGGGUUUCCUCUGCUCGCCUAAGUUACAGCACAAUACUAUGUGGACGUUUCAUUGAAAAUUUUACUUGAAAAAAUAAAAUUCCAGAUACUCAGGUGAGACACAAACCCACUGUUCCUGCUUUGAGACCUGUGAAUUCUUGUGGGACAGUUCCACUGACAGCUUGCGUUCCCGAGGUACCAGUCCUCAGUGACCUCGGGAACCCCAACCACUUAGGUCCCAAAGCCACAAGGGUGCCCUUUGUCUUGCUGGGAAGCUGGCUGAGGGCCUGCCAGGGCUGGAGGACCAGCUCUCCCGCACAGGGUUCAGGGCCUCUCCCAGAAAAAAGAGGUUUUGAAGUGAAAAGGCAACGAGGGGCCAGAGGGCUCCCCAGGAUGGGUCUUUUGGAGGUAGAUUUGAUGCCCACAACGCAUGCAAGGCUAAGACCCCCAACUUAGCCAACGAAGCCCAUGGCCUCAGAAGGGCUGCAGCUUGCUCAGGCCGUGGGCCAGGAUGCAUGCUGGACGGUUCUCCAAAUAAAAAAGCCCCAAGGGUUUGUCUACACUGCUUACCUGCUGGGGCUGUGAGUGGGGAGACGGCGGCCUGCCUAGGGCUCCUGGUGCCAGGCUCAGGAAGAGUCAUUCAUUGCAAAGGGCCGGCAAGUGAACCAGGGCCACCUCUGUCCCCAGCCUGUGAGAGGAGCAGCUAGCCCUGAGAAGGGCAAGGAUGAAUGAGGCUGACCACGUCACAGGAGUCCUCCAAGAGUGACGGGGAUUCAGUCAUCGGCCACAAUGGAGAGGGCCCGGAGCUCACUGAGUUUGGCCUCGUUCUCCCGCUCCCGCUGCUCAUCGGAGUGGCCUGGCUGGUC